AACUCUGCUCUGCCUGCAGUCUGGUGUGGACACACUGAUCAUACCUCCCGGAACCUGGGCCUCCCAGGGUGGCCUGGAGGCUGCAGACGGGCAGAGCAGCCAGGAGCUGCCCACCAAGGAGGCGUCUGGCACUGUCUGGGGUCCCGAGCUGGGAGCGGGGAUCCCCAGACACGGAGCUGGUGCGCCACCUGGAGUCCAUGUGGACUGGUGCAGCCCUCUGCCGUCCAGCCGGCAUCAAGGUGAGGCUGAGAAGCCACACAGAUCCACAGACAAGCACAGUGGCAAAGUCUGCAGAAGGCUCUGAGCCAGGAGGGAACCCUGGCAGGCUUCCUAGAGGAGGAGAUGUGAGCAGAGGCCAAGAUCUAGUUUCAAGGCUUUGUGGCUGAAACGGGAGCCCACGCCCGCCACAGCUGGCCACCUGCCUCUCUCCUGACUCCCGUGCAAGGCCAGUAAUGCAACCCAGGAGGGAGCCGCAGGGCGCCCUGGGUCCCCCACUCCCUUCUCCGGCCACCCCGUGGCUGUGCAUAGCUGCCCAGCAGAGCCCAUGCAGGAUGCUGCAGCCGGAGGGCCCCCAGGCCUCGGAGGAGGGGGGCCCCCGGAGGAGAGGACAGACUGCAUCAUCUGCUGCUCGGCCUAUGACCUCUCCGGGCACCUGCCCCGCCGCCUCUACUGUGGACACACCUUCUGCCAGGCGUGUGUGCGGCGGCUGGACACACCGGCGCCCGAGCAGCGCUGGAUCCCCUGUCCGCAGUGCCGUCAGAGCACGCCCACGCCUCGCGGAGGGGUGGCCAUGCUAGACCUGGACCUGGCUGCUUUCCUGGCGGUCAAGGCUGAGCGGGAGCCGGCAAGACUAGAACCCCUGCCCCUCACCUCCCUCAAAGGCAGCGCCAUCACUCGGCAGCCAGCUGGGCUGUGCCCUGCCCUGGGACCCCAGCCCCACUUCCCCCAGCCCAGAUACUGCUGCUGGGGCUGUGGCAGCCUCUGCUGCCCACCCCUAGGCAGCCCCGAGGUCUGAACUCUGGCCAUUCCCACCCCUGCAGGGGAAAUGCCUGCCUUGGAACCCCUGACCACACACCAUCAUGGGUUCAGCCCACUCAGAACAACCUGGCAGUAGCAUCCUAUACGCAGCUUCGUGUGGCCCAGCAGGGUGGUGUCAUCCCAGCCGUGAACAUCCCAGGCCACAGCCUAAGGUUGGGGGCUGGGAGGCUCCGCAGGAGGCUGGUGACCUCCCACCUGUCCUGGCCACAAUUACCAGACCCCAGACUAGCCCGACCGGAUGUGCCUGGUGAGGACACUGCUGUCUGAGUGGGCGGCAAGCCUGGCUUGGGCCUAGACGCAGCGCAAAGGAUGGCUCCCAAGAGGAUGCGAAGGCGUCCCGGGGGCCUGGGCUGCAGGCUGGAGGGGCAGGGCCGGUCUGGCUAUGCCUGGCGGGCUGCCCAGAGCAGGUCUCCCCUCUCCCACAGACGUCCCCGGGGUGUACCGGGAGGGUGGCAAGACUACCUCCUUCCUCCCUGCCCUGCAUGGCAGCCCUGUGAAUUCACCCACUCAACAAAGCUCAUGGAGUUCCCA